AGAGCAGGGCUUCCAGUAGCUGAUGGUAUGGUAGGAGGAGUGGAGUGGAGCUCUUGCCUUGUUACUGAGGAAAUCUAUUUGUUUCUAGUAUUACUGGAUUUUUGGGGAAAAAUUUGUAGUCCUCCCCUUGAAAGGCAAAGGGGCUAGUUGUGCCAUUUGCCUGCACAGGAACCAUGAGGAGACAUAUGGUAACUUAUGCCUGGCAGCUCCUGAAGAAGGAACUGGGACUGUACCAGCUCGCCAUGGAUAUCAUCAUAAUGAUCCGAGUGUGUAAAAUGUUCCGCCAAGGCCUCAGGGGAUUCCGGGAAUAUCAAAUCAUUGAGACUGCUCACUGGAAGCACCCUAUCUUCUCCUUCUGGGAUGUAAGCAGUUGGGCUCAGCAGGAUUAUGAGGGCUCAAAGAAGCCCAAUAAAUUGCAUCCCACUUCCUGGCCUAAGCUCAGAACUGAGAAAGAAGACAAAAGGAAAAGCAGAUGAGAGACCCAAUGGUCACUUUUAUUAAUGGCCAUACUUCUGUUGGAGAGGGUGACUUACAUCAUCAACCAAGAGGUUUACCUAAUACUGAACCCCAGAUUUAGACAGCCUUACAUGCCUAGCCACAGGCAACGCUGGACCAAGGCAGGCUCCACUGCAACAGCAGGCCUGCUGCCAAAACUCAUGGCAGGGAAAGGUGGAGCAAAAUAUGGGCUGAGAGGGAAGGAGACAAUCAUGCCUAGUUUUUCUCUUUCCAAAUUCAUCAAAGAGUUUAAGUCACUCCUCAAUGUAAAAGGAGAGAGGCCAGUAGUGUUCUACUAAUACACCUCCCUCCAUGUGGAAAGAAACCUUGGGAGUAGAGAGGUGGUCUCCAUUUCAAUGGUGAUCAAAAGAGCCAGAAGCAAUCCAGGAAUCACAAUAACCAGGGUUUUCUAAAUGCCCACACGCUCUCUCUAUUCGCGUCUCUACUUUCUUUCCUACACCCCUACUUCGGUGCAGGGGCAUUUUCAGGGCUUUGUUCACUGCGGUGACCAUGUUUCUUUUAUUUUUUUGAGACGGAGUCUUGCUCUGUUGCCCAGGCUGGAGUGCAGUGGCGCGUCUUGGCUCACUGCAAGCUCCACCUCCCGGGUUCACACCAUUCUCCUGCCUCAGCCUCCCUAGUAGCUGGGACUACAGGCACCCGCCACCACACCCAGCUAAUUUUUUGUAUUUUUAGUAGAGACGGGGUUUCACCUUGUUAGCCAGGAUGGUCUUGAUCUCUUGACCUCGUGAUCCACCUGCCUCGGCCUCCCAAAGUGCUGGGAUUACAGGCGUGAGCCACCGUGCCUGGCCUGGUGACCAGGUUUCUAGAUUUCCUAGAAGGUCCCAAUUUAAAAUAUUUUAUCCCAGUGGUAGAUCAUGUGCCCUUCUUUAGCUCAGAAAAGUUGGUCACCCUUCUGCUAACUUGUUCUAGUUCCCCAGAGGUAUCUUCAUUGCUACUGGGUGUGUUGCUCAGGGCUUCAAAGUUUCCCCAGCAAUCACCUGGACAAAUCCUGCCCAUUUUUCUGUUGUUUCAGGAAUGACUAGAGCCAGUCCCCACUCCUCUGCAUCUAGUGAUUCACUCCAAGAAAUUUCCCUAAAGGGCUUCUGACAGAUAGUGGCCAAAGAAAGGGGGAUACGGGGCUGGUGAUGGGGGAAGGAAAGGCAGCCUUAAACUGGUUUCUGAGGGGCCAGCAGGUAAUAUAACUAGUGUGUAUGUAGCUGAGUUUAAGAUACAGCAGGCCAGCUGGAGAGGAAAGAUACACCUCAUCUAAAGACAUUCAGAUACAAAUAUUAUAUUUUAAGACCCUGUGCUGGCCAAACCAAACAAGGCUGCAGCCCUGUGGUUGGGCUGAGAUGAAAAACGAAUGGAGUAGAAGAACUGUAACCAAAAGACUCAGGUUAGCUCUCAGGAAGGACCUCCUGACUCUCAGGGUGGCAUGUAAUGGUGAUGCAAUGGGCCCUGGAGAUCAGAGGGCUUUGGUUACCAGAAGACGUGGCCUGAUGCAUGGGGCAGUUGGAAGCUAAGAUGCAGAGUCACUUGUUGUCAGGGGAAUGUGAGGCUAAGCCUAACCACAUUGGCCAGCCAGAGUGGCUUGAGCAGAGCAGAAGCCUCUCAAGGGCAGCCUAUAAGGGUCAUAGGGUUGUCAGGCGGAGCACUGGGCGGCUGGAGUGCAGGAUCAGGUGGGGAGCCCUAGACUGCUUCAGUAGAUGUGUGAAUCUGGAUGUUUCUGAGCACUGCCUCUUUCCUUCAGUAGUCUCCCUGAGAAGCACCACAUGGCUAUGCAAAGGAUAAACACGUUGUGGGGGCGAGACGGGUCUGAGUCUAAGGAACAAAUGACAUGUGGCUUGAGGCCACACUCCAGACACGGAAUUGGGUUUGCUGAAAGCCUUGAGUUGGGGUCUCAGCUAGACCACUGACUUGCUGUGUGAUCCUUGGGCAAGUUCCUUCACCAUCUCAGUCCUACAUGGAGCUUAAUAAAACCUGCUUUGUCCUGAUGACUAAAUGGAGUAAGGCAGGGAGGAUACACUGUGCUUGGCUCAUUAAAGACAUUUAACAAA